AGAUGCGGUGGUGGCCGCCGAGCGCCUGGAAGGAGCUGCUGGACAGGCCGAGGGAGCCUCCGCCCGAGACCGCGCAGCCGCCGCCGCCAUGGGUAAGGCGAGCGGGCCGAAACCGAACGCUAGGCCCUCAGUCCCGGGCUGAGGGCCGCGGCCAGGCGGGGUGGACUGGGAGCUGGGGGAGACGCCGAGGCCGCCAGUCGGAACUGGGGCCCGAACCCAGGAUGGGCGGGGACUGCCUGGGACUCGGGGGCUCCCGGGGUCGUCAUGGCAACGCGCCCCCUCCCUUGUUCCGGCCCGUUCCCGCCCGGGUUCUGAGGCAUAGUGGCCGAGGGCUCGAGGUGCCACGGCGUCCAGGAGCGAGGACAGGGCCAGGCAGGGUGUCACUCCCGGGUCGGGGAGCAGGCGGGGAGGGGCGAUGACUUUUCAGGUUUGGGGGUGGCGGAGGGAAGACGCAUCUCAGGUUUUGGCCUGGGUGCCUGACGCCGAGGGCGGGAGACGGGGAAUGCUGACGCGCAGGAGCCUGGGUGAGCCCGCCGCGAUGGUCCUGGGGGGCCCCCAGGCCUCUGGGCAGCCUUGCUGGGGGGAGGGGGCAGGAAGAGAGGCAGGGAAGGGGCUCUAGGCCCCGGCAAGGUGCGGGCACUGGCCCUGGUACUCCUUGCGCGCCUGCGGCCGGGUUUGGGGGUCGCGUACGGGCCGGAGAAGUCCUGUAGCGCAGCCGGGGCGUGGCCGCGGUGUGAACGCCCCUCGGCGUGGGAACUGCCGGUGCCCAGCACCGAUCUGCCUCCCAGCAGCUGCAAAACACCCUUUGUGUGGUUGUCGCAUCGCACGUUAGGAAUUAUGAUGGGCUGUGUUAAAAAUGAGAGUUGCCACGGAUUAUGAAACAUGAAGUGGUUUCACUCCCGAAAAAUAGUGGGAGUCAGACCACGAUGCAGAUUUGAAGGAAUUCGUGUGUGGACAUUUUUCCACCAGGCAGUUUGGCCAUAGCAGUUGUGGCUGUUUGCAUUUUAGGUUGCUUAGGAUUCAGUGUCAGGCUUCAUGCCUAGCUAUCUAGAAAUCGGAGCUGGAAUACUAGAUCAUUGGAGACUCUGGGUUUUUUGUUGUUGUUGUUGUUCAGUGAAGGAAAAACGGGCACAUUGAUUACUUGUAAAUUUGUCAGAGAUUAUGAAAUGUUAUACUAAGUGCUUCGUUUUUCCACACCUUAGUUUUGUCAUCUGUGUUUGUUGAAGGUAUUCCCACCAGUCACAACAGUGAUGAGAUGAUGGGGAAGCGUCUGAAUUUCUAAGUAAACUGAGAAUAAAAUUUGCGGGAAGGAGGACAAUAUUUUUGUGAAUUGAAAAUAUCUUACUUGAUGAUACUGUGUCUUAAAAAUAUCAAUUAAAAAUCAGGCCUUUUAGAAUUUGCAUCUAUUAACUUGGUAUUCAGACUGGCGCUGUGGGCAUCCUCAACUGUGUGGAUGGCUACAAAAGACCCCACAGCUGUAGAGAGAGCAAACUUGUUAAACAUGGCUAAACUGAGUAUCAAAGGACUCAUUGAAUCUGCUCUGAGCUUUGGCCGCACUUUGGAUUCUGACUAUCCCCCCUUGCAGCAAUUCUUUGUUGUUAUGGAACAUUGCCUGAAACACGGUCUUAAAGUAAGAAAAUCAUUUUUGAGUUACAACAAAACCAUCUGGGGCCCUUUGGAACUGGUGGAGAAGCUGUACCCCGAAGCAGAGGAAAUAGGAGCUAGUGUCCGGGAUCUACCUGGUCUGAAGACCCCUCUGGGUCGAGCAAGAGCGUGGCUUCGAUUAGCCCUCAUGCAAAAAAAAAUGGCCGAUUACUUACGUUGCUUAAUUAUUCAGAGGGAUCUCUUGAGUGAGUUUUAUGAGUAUCACGCACUAAUGAUGGAAGAAGAAGGAGCAGUAAUUGUUGGGCUGCUGGUUGGCCUGAAUGUGAUCGAUGCUAAUCUGUGUGUGAAGGGAGAGGAUUUAGACUCACAAGUUGGAGUGAUUGAUUUUUCUAUGUAUUUAAAGAAUGAAGAAGAUAUUGGAAAUAAAGAAAGGAAUGUUCAAAUUGCUGCCAUAUUAGACCAAAAGAAUUAUGUUGAAGAAUUAAAUAGACAACUGAACAGCACAGUCAGCAGCCUCCAUUCAAGAGUUGAUUCAUUAGAAAAGUCAAAUACUAAGCUGAUUGAAGAGUUAGCAAUAGCAAAGAAUAACAUCAUUAAACUCCAGGAAGAAAAUCAUCAAUUACGAAGUGAAAAUAAAUUGAUUUUAAUGAAAACACAGCAGCACCUAGAGGUUACCAAAGUAGAUGUGGAAACUGAGCUUCAAACAUAUAAGCAUUCUCGUCAGGGGCUAGAUGAAAUGUACAAUGAAGCCAGAAGGCAGCUUCGAGAUGAAUCUCAGUUACGACAGGGUUCUGAAGAUGGCUUGAAAGAAAAAAAUGAAAUAAUUGCCCGACUAGAAGAAAAAACCAAUAAAAUUACUGCAGCCAUGAGGCAGCUGGAACAAAGAUUGCAGCAAGCAGAGAAGGCGCAAAUGGAAGCUGAAGAUGAGGAUGAGAAAUAUCUACAAGAAUGUCUCAGUAAAUCUGAUAGUCUGCAGAAACAAAUCUCCCAAAAGGAGAAACAGCUGGUGCAACUGGAAACUGACUUGAAGAUUGAGAAGGAAUGGAGGCAGACUUUGCAGGAAGAUCUUCAAAAGGAGAAAGAUGCCUUAUCUCAUCUUAGAAAUGAGACUCAACAAAUCAUUAGUCUUAAAAAAGAGUUCCUUAACCUCCAGGAUGAAAAUCAGCAGUUGAAAAAAAUAUAUCAUGAACAAGAGCAAGCUCUUCAAGAACUCGGCAACAAGCUUAGCGAAUCAAAACUUAAAAUUGAAGACAUAAAAGAAGCCAACAAAGCAUUGCAGGGACUGGUUUGGCUGAAAGACAAAGAAGCAACACAUUGUAAACUUUGUGAAAAGGAAUUCUCACUCUCUAAGAGAAAGCACCACUGUAGAAAUUGUGGGGAAAUUUUCUGUAAUGCCUGCUCUGACAACGAACUACCUUUGCCUUCUUCACCAAAACCAGUACGGGUUUGUGAUUCCUGUCAUGCACUGCUCAUUCAGAGAUGCUCAUCUAACUUGCCCUGAGACUCCAGAACUAAAUCCUUAUGUAUGAAAUUACCUACAAUGAAUGUUAUGAUGUUGUAUACAAAGGUAACCAGACAGCUCUCCUUAAGCGGCUUUCGGUCAGUAUUUGGUACCAGUUUAUCUUCUACAUAUUCAGCUCAUGGAAAUUACAAGUUAUAUAUUUCCUUCCCCAUUGUUUUUCAAAAUGUAUUUUCAACAGAGCAUGCUUAAAAAUCAUGUAACUCAUUAAAAGGCCAGAGAGCAGAGCUAACACAACUUGCCUUAUCUUGUAAAGGCCUUAAAAAUAAGGCUUCAGAUUGUUUUUUUCUUCUGAAUUCUGUCAAUUUGGUAUUUGAUGGUGCCUGCAGUUCUCUUAAUGCACUUUAAAGCUUCACAGUUCUGAAACUGGAAACGCAUAAAACUUUUAAAAUUAUUAAUAUUCUAAUUCAACAGAUUUUCAUUAUCUUUGUAAGAUUUCAACUAUAUUUAUUUGCCCUUUCUUCUCCCCCUCUCCCUUUGCCUCUUGCAUUAGACAGGGCCAAUAUUUUGUCCUACAAAAUUUCCUCUUGGUCUCUUUAAAAAUCAGUUAUUGUCGUGCUUGCUGAAGAUUUUCAGCUACAGUGGAUUAAAUUAAAGGGGGCAUUAUUUGGCCUCGGCCUCUACUUUUUUCCUUUUAAUCUUGAAAGGAAGUUACAUAUAACCAUCUUUCUUUUCCUGAUUUAUAAAUCUUCCCAUAUGCUGUUUCAUUAAAUUGCUGUUUUUUUAAGGGGUGACUCAGACCCCAAUUCAAAGAUGAAAACACAAAUCCUUCCCCAGAAAAAAAAGUAUGUAAUAGUAGGGGAUGUUACAGGCUCCUUAUAAAGGUCCUCUCCUCUAAGCAUUAAAAGUGAGAAAAAAAUCAGGACUUUGCUUUGGUAAUGUAUUAGAGUUCAGUUCAAAAAAUUUUGUAUUAACAUUUUCAUUGGAGUAAAUUUUAGGAAGUAUCACAUUGUAGUGGCCUACCUGUAUACAUCCACAGUAAAAUUUCACCAUGUCCAUUGAGCACCUCUAUGCCAAGGGUGUUGAGAUGAUGAAAUAUACACUUGACCUAUUUCUUUUUUUUUCGAGAUGGAGUUUCACUCUUGUUGCCUAGGCUGGAGUGCAAUGGCACGAUCUCCACCUCCUGGGUUCAAGCAAUUCUCCUGCCUCAGCCUCCCAAGUAGCUGGGAUUACAGGCGUGAGCCACAGCACCUGGCCAGUACACUUGACCUAUUUCAAGCUGACUCAAUGAACACUAAUCCAAGUUAUAUUGCUUAUGGCAUACUAAGAAUUUAACUUGUAUAAAUUACCUCUGAAUAGUUACAUAAACACUAUCACCAUUCAGUAUCCUAUUUUUUACAUUAAUUUUUAACCAUGCACUUUAAGUUUGUGAGCCUAUAAAAAAUACAUAGAAAAUUUAUGGAUUAAGAGCAUUAUAUUUAGUGGUUAAUCCUAGGUACCUCCCUGCCUACAAAGGAGUUCUUAUUAAUACUGCAGGAUCUUUUCUUCAUGAAUAUAUGCUUCCAUGAAAUUUAAAUUUUUCUGAAUAGCCUAAGUAUGAAAUGAAUAUUUUACUUGAAGAUCUAUUUUUUCCAAAACCCGUAAAUUUCCAGUCAGCUUUUGAGGUGUCAGAUGUGACACAGAUUUCUAGAUGGUCUUUCUUGAAUACUGACAGAAAUGUCCUCAAGAGAGGAUUAUAUUCUUGAACCAUUUUGUAUUGAUAGGUGGGAUGGGCUAACAUUUUUAUGAUUACUGAAUAAACAAAAAAUGAAAUUUUCAAAUAUGCUUUUUUAUUACUGUGCUUAGAACAAAUUUUAAAAUGUGACUUAAGUUGCUUAAAUUCCAAGGCUAAUUUCAUUCAACAAACCAUGAUUUUGUCAUCCUUUAAGUAAGUUUCUCACUUUUCAAAACUCAUGUAUCAACACUGACUGACUUGCUUUUUUUUUUUUUUUUUUUUUUUUUAGGCAGCUUUUAUGACAGCAACUUGCUCCAUGUAGUUUUGGCUUAUUUAAAAACUAUACUAACUUUGGAUUUUUCUGUUACAAGACUUUUAACAAUCUGUAUUUCGUGAUUGUGAACUCGUAUUCAUUUUACUUUUCAAAAACAGACUUAACAUACCAUUCCCUCACCUAGCAGUACUACCACAAUAAUGCUAUCAUGGUGCCAGGGAAUUACAAUUGUAAUUCUUCUAACCUAUAAUGUUUAAAAAAUAAAAUGUGAAUUUUAUGAACUAAAUAAAUAUUUGGAAAAUUAGCCUGCUUUAAAAGGGCAAUUUUGGUUUCAUUAAUACUGUAUACUUUUACUGCUUUAAGAUGUUAAGAGAGUAAUCCUGGGAAAAUAAAACACAUACAACUUUCAAAAAA